GGAUAGCACAGGCACGUCCCGGGGGCUCCAGCUUCUGCUCAGAGCGCGGAGAGCCGGGCCGGGCGGGCGCGCGCGCAGGACUCGGGCCGCUCGAGGGGUCCGGCCGGACGGUGUCGGGAGCCGGACCCGUCGGCAGAGGAGCGGGCGCCGCGAUGGCUGAGGGCAGUGCCGUGUCUGACCCUCAGCACGCCGCGCGUCUGCUGCGAGCGCUCAGCUCUUUCCGCGAGGAGUCUCGCUUCUGCGACGCGCACCUGGUCCUCGACGGGGAGGAGAUCCCGGUGCAGAAGAACAUCCUGGCGGCGGCCAGCCCGUACAUCAGGACAAAGUUAAACUAUAAUCCUCCAAAAGAUGAUGGAUCAACUUAUAAGAUUGAACUUGAAGGGAUAUCGGUAAUGGUUAUGAGAGAGAUCCUGGAUUACAUCUUCAGUGGGCAGAUCAGGCUAAAUGAAGAUACAAUCCAAGAUGUUGUUCAGGCAGCUGACCUGCUGCUACUGACGGACCUUAAAACCCUGUGCUGUGAGUUUUUGGAAGGCUGCAUUGCUGCUGAGAACUGUAUUGGUAUCCGUGACUUUGCACUACAUUACUGCCUCCAUCACGUUCAUUACCUUGCCACAGAAUACCUGGAGACUCAUUUCCGAGACGUCAGCAGCACGGAAGAAUUCUUAGAGCUGAGUCCUCAAAAGCUUAAAGAAGUGAUUUCUCUUGAGAAGUUAAACGUUGGCAAUGAAAGAUAUGUCUUUGAAGCAGUAAUUCGAUGGAUAGCACAUGAUACAGAAAUAAGAAAGGUCCACAUGAAGGAUGUUAUGUCAGCUCUGUGGGUUUCAGGGUUGGACUCCAGUUAUUUACGGGAACAGAUGCUGAAUGAACCAUUAGUACGAGAAAUUGUCAAAGAGUGUAGCAAUAUACCGCUCAGCCAGCCGCAGCAAGGGGAGGCGAUGCUGGCCAACUUCAAACCCCGGGGCUACUCUGAGUGCAUCGUGACUGUUGGUGGAGAAGAGAGAGUUUCACGGAAACCCACAGCAGCGAUGCGAUGCAUGUGCCCUCUCUAUGACCCUAACAGGCAGCUUUGGAUCGAACUGGCCCCUUUAAGCAUGCCGAGAAUUAACCAUGGAGUUCUCUCAGCAGAAGGAUUUUUGUUUGUAUUCGGGGGCCAAGAUGAAAAUAAGCAGACUCUUAGCUCAGGAGAAAAGUAUGAUCCAGAUGCAAAUACAUGGACAGCAUUGCCACCUAUGAACGAGGCAAGACAUAACUUCGGAAUUGUGGAGAUAGAUGGGAUGCUGUACAUUUUGGGAGGAGAGGAUGGUGAAAAGGAGCUGAUUUCCAUGGAGUGUUACGAUAUUUAUUCUAAAACCUGGACAAAGCAACCUGAUUUGACCAUGGUCAGAAAGAUCGGCUGCUAUGCAGCUAUGAAAAAGAAAAUCUACGCCAUGGGUGGAGGCUCCUACGGAAAGCUUUUUGAGUCUGUAGAGUGUUAUGAUCCCAGGACCCAGCAGUGGACUGCCAUAUGUCCACUAAAAGAGAGGAGGUUUGGAGCGGUGGCCUGUGGAGUUGCUAUGGAGCUGUAUGUGUUUGGGGGAGUCCGAAGUCGUGAGGACGCCCAGGGUAGCGAGAUGGUAACUUGCAAGUCCGAGUUCUACCAUGAUGAGUUUAAAAGGUGGAUCUAUCUUAACGACCAGAAUUUAUGCAUCCCCGCCAGUUCCUCUUUUGUUUAUGGAGCUGUACCUAUAGGAGCCAGUAUUUAUGUUAUUGGAGAUCUUGAUACAGGUACCAAUUACGACUACGUGCGUGAGUUUAAAAGAAGCACAGGAACCUGGCACCACACUAAACCACUCCUUCCAUCCGACCUUCGCCGUACAGGAUGUGCAGCCUUACGCAUUGCGAAUUGCAAGCUUUUCCGCCUGCAGCUUCAGCAAGGCUUAUUCCGUAUUCGUGUUCAUUCCCCUUGAGGAGGAAGCAGAGCAGAGUGCGAGAUCCUGACCCAAGAGCACCAUAACAUAGCUCCGAAAGGGAGAGCAGAGAUGGCAGCUGAAACUCACUCUGUGCUGGGCUUUGGUAUGGUAACUCUUUGGUGGUUUUAUGAUGCUUACAAACUUGAGCUUUAGCUCUUGUUUGGGAGAACACGUAACUGUUGAAAAACUACCUGGGAGGAGUGAGUUCCUCCAGUUAAAUGUGGCUGUAGAUGUUGGAGGCUAGGGAGGCUAGUAAAUAUCAAAAGGAAAAGGGAGUGGGAAUUGCUAUCAUGUAAAAUAUCAAAGUUAAAAUACUAAGGUGCAUUUUCCCUGAAGGGAACUCAUGUCUGACUGCUGUAUUCAAAUACGUAGCUUUGGUAACAAACAAAAUCCGUAUAUGCAAAUCAACAUAUCCAAACAUGCCAAGACUGCUUUUCCACUGCACUUGGAAGGAUAUAUUAUGCCUAACCCUGCCCAACAAAUUAAGGUUUGUGCCUAAAAUGUUAGAUUGGACUGUAUGCCAGUUAGUCUCCAUUUAUUCCUAGUACUCUGUCCUAAGAAUCUUUUUAAAACUAUAUCAUGAUGAAUUGAAAUGAAGAUAAAAUUGCUCUUUUGUAACUUUAUCUUAGUAAUGUAAAGAUUCAGUAAAUUGAUGAGUCAGGUUGCAGCCCUCAUGUGAACUGAAAGAAGUUGCUCGCUUCUGUGUUGACUUAGAUCAAGACACGUCACGCAUCCUUUCUGGGGUAGUACCUGUGGAGCCGGGAAGGGUCUCCUGCAGUGCCAUUCUGCCUUCUCAAUGAGCAAAACCAUUUUCUAAGUAUGAGGAUAUUAGUGAGUAGGAGAUUUUAUAAAAGAAAGACCUGAGUCAGACAAAUAAUAAAGGUCUGCUGUGGCUAAAAAAGCAAAAACAAAAAAGCUAUCCAGACAAAAUACAUAGGGAUCAGAAACUUUUUCAUAUAACCUGUCUGAAAGCACACAAAGUCUUGUUUACUACUGUUUAGGGUUUGAAAACUUGUCUUAGAAUGCGAAUCUGUGUUAAGAAUCUAGUCUUUGUAAUAGAAGUUUCCCAGUGGCAUUCACUAGUGAGAGUUUUAGACAAAUUAUGUUACGAGUAAAGUUUGGCUGGUAGAAUAAACUACCUCAACUUAAUUUCAUUCUGUUCAUAGUAGAGCAAAUUAAUCUUUUCCUCCUUCCCUCCUUUCCUAUCUCUCAUUCUCACCUCAACCCACUUUACCCCACUUCUCAUUGGGGGAAAAAUGUCUUUCGUUCGUGGAACGUAUCUUGUAAGAUAUUUUGUUUUCCACUUGAAUUACACCACCCUAGUGUGAAAUCGGGGACUUCAAAGUGCUUGAUUCCUUCCUAAAUUGAAUUUUAUGCAAUGUCAAAUUUCUAAUCAAUUUAAUAUACAGUACUUCAUUUUUAAUUGUUUUCUAAAAAAAAGGUUUUUUUUUUCCUUUUGGAAUAUGGCUGUAAGAAGCAGCAUUUUGUCUUAUUAACACAUGUAUAAAGGUAUCCUUUGGUUUUAAGUCGAGAACAGGAAUUUCUUCUAGAAACUUCCUGUAUGGAACGUUUAUAUGCAAUUAACAUGCAUAUGAAAAACAUCACUUACGUUCUCCCACCCAUAGACAUAAAAAAGGGUGACCUGUGAUUUUUUUUCUUAUACCUGCUGGAAGUCAGUACAAUGCGUCAAAAGUUGCUGAAAGAUGCUGUGCCUAUGGGGUUCUAGAGAGUGUUGAGUGUGGUACAUUAACUCUCCAUUUUAGCCAGAAGAUACCUGAUAAGAGAAGGUGUAAGGUUUUUAUCUUAUAUGCCAGAGGCACCAGGCCAGAUGUGCCGCACAGUCAUGUAAUUCAAUCAUGUUUAAUAUGUCAGUCAAAACCAAAUUCAGAAUUGUUUUGUGUACCAGUCAGCUGUUGUCUGCACAUUUUCGUAGUGACAGUGUGGAGAUCUUUUUAAUGAAAGCAAACUAUGUGGCCUCUGCAAAGAAAGGAAGAUUUUUCUUUUUACAACUAGAUAUUAGUUUUAGAGGAAGGAAAUAGCUGAAAAACUAAAUUUGCUUUGGUGAAAUGUCCUGUACAGAACAGUACCUUGGCAUUCAGCAGCUGUAAUUGGGGAACAUUAAAACAGUAACUGACAUCCAGUUAAAGCCACGAUCGUCAGCAAUUCUCCUUUUUUAAUUUCUGAUAUUUAAAGUUUUUUUUCCAGUCUACACCAGGCCUCUCCAAGGAGACAGUUCAUUAUUUAGGAGUGAAUGUGUUCCUCUUGCAAUAUUAUCAGUACCUGCAUGACUUGGUAAAUUCAUUUUAUAAAAAUAGUGUUUUUUUUUUUUAAUUUCAGUUCAUUGACUCUAUAACUGCAGAAAUUAGAUAAUGUUUUAUAAAAUAAAUUUGCCACAUAAUAUGGGAUGCAAUAACCAACAAAGCUGCUAAGUGCCAAACUGUUAUUUUACUAUAUAUAAAUAUUAAAAUAUUGUGUUGAAGUAUAGGGAUGUAUUUAAUUUUACUAUGCUCCAACAUUAAUCAUGACUCUUUUGUAAAUUACAGUUAUUUCAGUAUUGUAAAAUAAAUGUUGACUCAUUUCAUGCAGGUUUGUGUUUUAACAUUCCACUUAUGCCUUGAAACAUCAUUUCUUGAUAACUUUUUGAUACUUCUUUCUUGAUAAGGCACUUUUACCAGGUGUGUGUUGGAAUUGGUGGCUCAGGAUAGGUCUUAAAUUUUAAAUACAAAUAUCUUUGGGGGAAGUGCAAUUUAUUUUCAGAAGGAAAGUUGUCUCAGGUUAGAAUAAGUAAAUAUUUAAAGAACCUCUCCUAGGCUGCAGUCUAAAAUAGGUAGUUUGUUUCUUUGUUUAGCAUAUCCAAAUUUAGAUUUUUCAAAGAUUUAAGUGUUUAUUGAAAGUGUUUUUUGUUUUGUUUUUGAUAGUGCUUAUAUCCUGUGAAUAGAAAAAGUGUGAGAGAUGAAUGAGUGAGUUGUACGUGUGUGUGUGAUGCUAUUUGACCUGAUAAAUGUAUUUGUGUUUACUUUUUGAAUUGUAGUUCUAAACUACAUAUAUUACUGUCUCCUGGUGCUUCAGAUAAAUUCUUGAGCCUGUUGACCUUCAGUUUAUACUACUGUGUCGAACUCAUAUUGAGUGUAAAUAUUGAAAUAUUUGUAGUUUAUAGUAAGUUUUACUUGGUGUUCGCGUUUCUCUUCUUCAGCAGGAUUAAAAACAGUGUUUACCAACUCGUAGUUGGUAUACUGUCAGGAUUUGGCCUAAGAAAUUUCUGAAUGCAUUGUUUAGCUUAGUACUUCAUUGCUGUAAGGAAUUGAUAGCUAACUGUAGGCUUUUUUCAAACUGUAUAACAACCAAAAAGGAGCAUUUGGGGGUAUGUUGGAUGGUGUUUUGUUUGUAAACACUUUGUUAUAUUGCACUACCACUUUAAUGAUGACACUUCCUUCAUUGAUGGCUUGGAAGUGUCAUUUUUAUAAUUUAUGAGUUGGGGGGAUUCCCUAGUCAAUGCAUAGGAAAUACAUUCUUUGUACAAACGUGGUAAAGAGAGGACUGGCUUUGCUAUGGCACCUAAGUUACUCAUGGGUAGUUAAGUUUCAUUUCUAGAGAAAUGUCUUAGCUGCUGUGGUCCAUUAGAGUUCCCUUUGGUACAUUCCUACCUCAGUGUACCAAACCAGGGAUUCCAAAAACCUUCCAAGGAGUGCUAGAAACACCGCAGUAUCCCCUUCCAGAAUGUUGGCGUUCAUGAUUCAAGAGGCCUCCCGUGGUCAGAUGAAGACCUUUGGUUAAAUGGGGGAAGAAUGAGGUGGCGCUUUGACUGUAUCAAUUUAAAGAUGCCGGAACCCCGUUAAAAACACCUGGUGGAAGGGAAAGGUGAGGCGGCCCUUUUCCACUGGCUGCUCACUGAGCACUGGAGUCCAGGAAGUCAGUGAGAAGAGAGCAGCUGAGUGUAGCAAAACCCGCCUUGGGUCAGCCAACACAUGUCUGAUGAGCACCCACUAGGAACUGUGCUUGCCAUCCUGGGAGCUGAACAGUGAGGCAGAGGUCACACCACUCUCCUACUCAAGGUCAUAAACCCACUAUGGAACGGGCAAGGGCCCCGUCUUUGUCAUCUGCCAGUCUCAGUGCUUGCACAGAGUAGGUAGGCAAUAAACAUUUGACAAAUAAAUAUAAGAUUCUUGUGAUCAAAGUAAUGUUCUUCUGUUGAAAAGGGCACUCCAAGAGUGACUGAUUUUACUGGGUUUUCAGUGAGAAACUUUGUACCCAUAUGGGCUGGCCUCCUAUACGGAGCUGAAACUAGCAUGGGCCGGCCUCCUAUAUGGAGCUGAAACUAGUAUAGCAUAAACAAUGCCAAGUGCCUGAUGUACAUGAUGUACAGUCUUCUGAUUGUACCCUCUAUAUGGGACUAUGAGACCCUCUAUAGACUCAGCACAGCUUAUAAUGUUGAUCAUGUUUAGUAUUGGGCUUUAUUGACUGCUUUUUAUAUGGGUGUCAAAAUCUUUCCAGGACAUACCCCUUUGAUCCUCACACCUCUGGAAUAGGCAGGGCACUCUCCCCAUUGUACCAGGGUAAUCUUGGAGGCCUGAUAGAUAUGGCUUCAUUUCUCACUUUAGGGAGGAGCAAGAACCAAAAGCAGAAGCCAGGUCUUUGGAUUAUCAGCUCACCAGUCAGCCAGUGAGGCUGGAACUUGAUUUUUCUAGGCAUACAAGUAUUUUUAGUAAUAGAAUAAUCAUUUUUAGUAUUAAUACAAUUUACGCUCCCAAACAUGUCCUUUGCUAGUUGCACAGGCAUAAGCUGAAAGAUCUUUGAUUUUCUUUGUUAGUUAGCUAUAGGAAGGUUAAGAAUUUAUUUACUAAGGUCGUAAGAACAGAAGAAAGUUUCUUUGAAAGAGAAACUGUUUUUUUAUUUCAAAGAGCUUCAUGUAUACUUCCCUCUCUUAUUCCAUGUAAUUAGUAAGGGAAAAUAAACUAUGUCUUAGAAUGUUGAGGAAAGUAUUUUGAUAGCUUUUAAUAAUUCUUGAAAUACUCUUUACUCUGUCUGUAGUUUUGAGAAAUUACAGAAAUUCAUAGUAUAAGGAUGAGAAGGGGCCCAUUUGCCCAUAUUUGAUAACACAGACUUGGAUUGAGUGUCUGUCAUGCCUGCUGGCAGUUAAGUCUCAGUGGUAUUGACUGCUAGGCAUUUUCUAUAUUUUUUGCAAGUUAGCUGGUAAAACUUGGUAAAGUUUUGUGUUUUUCAGAAGGAACCCUAUUAUUAUUUCCAUUUUAAACAUAUUUCAAUAUUGUCUCAUUGUAAUAGUUCCAUUUAUGUGACAUCUGAGGAAUUAAAUCAUACUUCCAGAUGGUUUGGUCUAAUGUAUACAGUUUAGGAAAGUUUAUUCUUUUUUAUUUUAUUUUAUUUUUUUAAAUUUCUUUUAGAAACUGGGUUUUGCUCUGUUGCCCAGGCUGAUCUUAAACUCCUGGCCUCAGAUGUGGAGACCCAGCUGGGACUACAGGCAUGAGCCACCACGCUCCGUAGAAAGUUUGUUCUUUUUCAGUUCUGUCAUUGAAAUUCUCUAAGUGAUUGGAUUUUUAAACCCCUUCCCCUUUUCAUGAAAUUAAACAUCAAAUAAAUAAAACUACAUUAUAUAAUUAUUUAGUCAGAAAUGACUGUUGCCCUCUCUUUUUUUUUUUUUUUUUUUUUUUUUUUUGAGACGGAGUCUCGCUCUGUCGCCUAGGCUGGAGUGCAGUGGUGCGAUCUCGGCUCACUGCAAUCUCCGCCUCCUGGGUUCAAGCAAUCAUCCUGCCUCAGCCUCCCCAGUACCUGGGAUUACAGGUGCUUAUUACCACACUCGGCGAAUUUUUUGUGUUUUUAGUAGAGACGGGGUUUCACCAUGUUAGCCAGCAUGGUCUCGAUCUCCUAAACUUCGUGAUCCGCCCGCCUCAGCCUCCCAAAGUGCUGGAUUACAGGUGUGAGCCACCUCGCCUGCCCUCUUUUUUUUUUUUUAUUUUGAGAUUAAAACUAAUUCUUUUAAAGUCACUACUCAGCUGAAAUUUGGCCUGAUUAUAAAUGUUGAUAAUAAUUUCUUCCUGGCUCAACAAAGUUGUUGAGCUUCCUUCUGUGCACACAUUGAAAGAAAACCAGAAAUUGUACAGUCGUGAUAUGAAUUAGAGAAGGAACAGGUGGAAAAGGAUGGCAACACACAGAGUCCGGGGGACACACGGCCUUAAGAUGAAGUGAACGAGUAGACACUGAAUAGGAUCCACGUAAAUGAACGGCCAUUUCAAAUCAUUCACAUCCCAAACGGAGGUUCAUCUGUCUUCUGGUUGGUGAAUUAUAUUUAUUAGGAUCUUAUUUUUAGCAUUUCAUUACAAGUAAUAGGUUUGGGUACCUUAUUUUUAUUGUUUUUACUCAUCAGUUAUGAAUAAGGCAUACCUUAGAAACUUGGGUUAAAUUUUUUCAAGUUAUACCAGUCAACUUGGUUUAAAUACAACUGUACUAACUUGCUUUAUCAUGUUUCCUGUUUAAUUGGAUGAGAAUUACAUGCACUUAUUCAGUUGUUCUUUGUGUUUAUAGGAAAAACUCUGUUCUCAGCUACCUCAUUAUGUAGUAUUGUGCUUGAUCCCCUGCCAAUUGAGAAGAAUUCAACACAUUCUGUUCUUUAACAAAAGCUUGGAAGCAGGCAGUCAGAGGCCUUGAGGAAUACAAUUCUCUAAGGCCUGUUUUCCAUUUUACUACUUAAAAAAAAAAAAAAAAGAAAAGAAAAAAAAGCACUUACAACCAGGAGGAAUAAUAAUUCUCCUAGAGUUGCUGCAAACUGAUUACUUGAAACUCAACUUGAACUUUAAAGAGUCUUUAAAAGGCUGUUUUCAUAAUGCAGAAAAGUAGUCUAUUUAAACGCCACUGCUGUGUAAAACAGGGGGCUCGAUUUCCAUUCUUGUUAGCAUCAGACAAGAAAAUGUGUCUAUCUGUCAUCUGACCCAGUAUUUGGGAUUUGGGUGCUUGAGGAUACUAUUUUUUUCAUUUCUUAUAAGGUGCUAUUGUUUCCCAGAAAUCUUUAAUUUUGAUGAAAAUCUACUCAUUGCUAAGAUCCUCCUCACUUAAAGUGUUUCCUCAGUGCAGAGUUGAGGUUGGCAGAACUAUAUAGAGUUGGAUGAUACUGAAAAUCAUGAAUGAUGUGAUUUGUUCCAUGUAUCUGUGGAACAUCCCUCACCUUCCUCCGGUAUGCGCCUUCUGCACUCCACACGUGGUCGCCUCCAUCCUCCCUAGUGUCUGUCAGCUUGCCUGGUCACCAAGUCAGGAGGAAGAAGAUGAGGAGGCUCACCAGUUGUAGGCAAGACUCUUCCUCUCGGGAGAUCUUGUAAUAAUGGCCCAGUUUCAGGGCACAGUUGUACACAUUCUACUUAAAUGGAGGAGUUCAGUGAUGCCGUGGCCAAAAGAGUUAUGCCCAUUUCUAAAAGCCUGGCAUAUUUGGUAUAACUUAAGCACCAGGUAAAAUCUGGUGCUUAAGUUGUACCAAGUAUAGCCAAGUUUAACUGUCGUUGUGUAUUAAUAAGAUUUAAUUUUUAUGCUUGUGCUUUUCAGAGUAAAGGGCUUGCUUUCAAUAGUAGAAUGACAAAGCUUCUCCUCCAAUGACAAUCUGUUAGCACCCUGUUGACUUAGCUCAGGACAUGAGACUGACUUAGCUCAGGACAUGAGACAUUUCCUGGAAGUGAUUUCCAUGAGAACAAAGGCUUAUUCCUUUAACUUAAACCCCAAACUUUGUUAUUUUAAUUAUUUUCAGGCAAUCAUCUUUAUAUACUUUCCUUACAAACCCAGUGGUUGAGAGCAUAGGCCUUGGUGGCAGGUGCAUCUGGGCUUGGGGGCUUCUGCCACACUUACUACUCUGUGACUUGGGAAGCUCUUAAGGCUCCCAAGGCUCCGUUUCUUAUGUGGAAGAAGAAUAGCAGGAGGACUCACCUCUGCGGGUUGUUGUGAGGAUUAACUGGGUGAUGACUGUAAGCAGCUGGGAGAGUGCCUUGUGUGCAGUGACCACUGUUGCUGCCACCAUGAUUAUGUCACCUCUCAACAUGGGGUGGUGGGAGGCCCUGUGGAUGAGGCCAAGGCUGCCUGCACUGAGUGUCCCAGGCCUUAUAGCUUUCCACAUUCUCACGUCUGCUGCCACAUGAUAUACAAGUAAAUGUAUUAGAAGUUGGUGUUCAUAAAAUACUUUUUUUUUUUUUUUUUUUUGAGAUGGAGUCUCGCUCCGUCACCCAGGCUGGAGUGCAGUGGCGCCAUCUCCCAGGCUCAAGGGAUCCUCCUGCCUCGGCCUGCCAAGUAGCUGGGACUACAAGUGCACACCAGUAUGCCCAGCUAAUUUUUUGUAUUUUUAGAACAGGUGUGGUUUCACCAUAUUGCCCAGGCUGGUCUCGAGCUCCUGAGCUCAGGCAAUCCGCCUGCCUCAACCUCCCAAAGUGCUGGGAUUACAGGUGUGAGCAUCCAGCCAGAAAAUGAUUUGCUUUCUAGACCCAUAUCACCUCUCUCCAUCUACAUCUCUAGUAUUUAAAUUCAACACAAUUCUAGAUAGCUGAAACAGCCCAAAAUAUGUGUUUAGAAUACUUAGAGUUUGUUAUAAAUAACCCUCUGUUUAGAAUUUGCCCAGUGAAAUUCUCUAAUAAUACUUAAAACUCUUUACUAAAGUUGAAUUUUCCUUUUUUUUCAUUGAAAUAGCAAAGGUAGUAAUCUGUAUUGGUCAAAGAAACGAGAUAAUUCCUAGAUCUCUGUUUUAGACCAGUAGACCUAACUGUGCUUUCUUAACUUGGAUGUUACAUGAAACUUAAAAACAAACAAAUAUGUGUUACAAGUACUUGUGUGUACGUGCAUGUGUGUUUGUGCAUGUGUCUGUGUGUGUGGAACUUUUGUACCUUUGCAUAAAGAAGGUUAUUUAACAAAGUGGUACAAACAGUGAACUACUUAAUCCUUCUAUGGUAUCAUACACUUCUUUUCCUGGUUAGGUUAUGAGACUGGCAGAGGUAGGAGUAUAUAAUGUGCUCAGCUUGUCUUGAUUUCAAUAAGACAUUUGAUAAAGUCAUUCUUGAUCUCUGAAUGUGAAAAGGAAGUAGAACAGCCGGGCGCGGUGGCUCACGCCUGUAAUCCCAGGACUUUGGGAGGCCAAGGCGGGCAGAUCACCUGAGGUCGGCAGUUUGAGACCAGCCUGACCAACGUGGAGAAACCCCGUCUCUAUUAAAAAUACAAAAUUAGCCGGGCAUGGUGGCACAUGUCUGUAAUCCCAGCUACUCGGGAGGCUGAGGCAGGAGAAUCUCUUGAACCCAGGAGGCGGAGGUUGCGGUGAGCCGAGAUGGUGCCGUUGCACUCCAGCCGGGCAACAAGGGCUAAACUCCAUCUCAAAAGAAAAGAAAGAAAGGGAAGUAGAAGUAGGAUUUAACAAAGGACCGAGAAGUCGGCUGAAUAGCCAGGUUCAGACAGUGUUGGCAAGAACGGAUCUUUGGCAAGAUCACUUAAGGUGAGCUACUCUAGCAGCAUCCUGUUUGACAUUUGUAUCCAUAACUUGAAUAAAAAUAUAGAAGGCAAAGAAGAGUGCUGGGCAAGAUGUGUUGGGUGUUAGAUCUGCAAUACUCUUCAUAGUGUAAUGGCUAAAUGUAAAGUCUUACGUCUCGGUUCAAGAAAGCACGUUGCUAUAUGAAAUUUCAGAAAAAAGUUUUGUUGCGGGGGGUGGGAUAUUGAUCAUUUGAACAUAUGCCAGUUGUUUCUCCUGCCCUAGGGGAGGUUGGCACGGCAACCUUCCCACUCCGUAGGUGGGUAGCCUUGCUGAUGGGGCACGUCGUCACCAAGGGACCUGAUUGUUGUCAUGGUUUUGUCUUGUCCUCCUCCCUGGUGAAAGUCUACUGCAGUUUUAUUCUCAGCUCUGGAAGGAGAGGGAACGAGCCUCUGCCUGUGUGUCCUGACCCCUCUUGCCUUGUUUUUGAUCUGCUCAGGCCGGGUGCAGUGGCUCACGCCUGUAAUCCCAGCACUUUGGGAGGCAAAGGCAGGUGGAUCACUUGAGGUCAGGAGUUCAAGACUAGCCUGGCCAACAUGGUGAAACCCCGUCUCUACUAAAAAUACAAAAAUUAGCCGAGUGUGUUGGUGGGCCCCUGUAAUCCCAGCUACUCGGGAGGUUGAGGGAGGAGAAUCACUUGACCCCAGGAGGCAGAGGUUGAAGUGAGCCAGGAUUGUGCCACUGUACUCCAGCCUGGGCGACAGAGGGGGACUCUGUCUCACAAAAAAAUAAAAAAUUAAAAAAAAAGGUCUGCUCAGAAAUAGGGGAAACACGGGAUCAAGAUCAUUAGAGAUUUAUAGGCUGGGAUGCACACCAUGUCUUCAGAGCUAGCCGGCUGUGUCUUCUCCCCGUUUCUUUCACUGGUGAAUAACCUUUCGUUUGAACCAGCCUUGAUUGUUCUCUCCAUGUUCCACUGUGGCUCCCCAUGGACACUGCUAGGUGGAAUCUCUGAGAAAACAGGCACUUCGCAGUCGGCGCAUCUUUCUCUGCCAGCUUAGGGAUUGCCGUCAAGGUGGAGGAAGGGUAUUUUGGCCAUGUUCGGAGUCGUUGUUUUUACUCACUCUUCUUGGGAUAGCUUUCCCACCCUGCCCUCUGCUCCUCUGUCCCAACCCUCUUCCAGCCUGGUUUUUUUACUGCUUGAAUUAUGUAUCCAAAAUAAAAAGGAAAAGAAAGGUGCAGUUGGGGCGGGUUGUUGGGGGCGAGGAGAAUAGCCCUUCUGGUUCUUCAGACCACAUAAUGGCCAGAGCAUGAGCCUCACAGAUCCCUGAGCAGACCUGCAUACUAGCACUUUCCACAACCAGCUGGCCCUGGCUGUGAGAGUCAGAUCUGUCCCCAAGGCUCCAGGUCAGAACUUGGACCCAGGUGCCUUCUGAGGCACCGCCAAGGACACAUCCCAGCGCCUUAGGCACCUGUAGGCUAGAAUGACACCUUCCAGGCCAGCCCCAGAGGCCCUCAGGGCUCCCCCUCCAAGCCGGGAGGGCAGGCAGGCACAGGCCCCGCUCACUACCUCAGCACCCAGUGCAGCCCCAGGCUCCCGGACGUGCUCGGCCCGGUGGCCUCUUGUGUGACAGGCCCUCUGCCAUGUCUGUCCGCAGAGCCGGGUGGGGACCCUCCGUGUGGGUCCUCCUCUGUCCCUUUGCAGCUCGCAUUCGCCAGAGCGGAGCGCAGCCCUUGUUUCCUUCUUUCCUCUUCAGCUCUGACUUAAAAACACACUAUGUUCCAAAUCGUUGUGGGAUCGGAAACUAGAACUGCUUGUUUCCAGGAGAGACCACCUUUUCAUAUUUUUUUUAAAAGGAAUUUGUGCUUCAAAAGAAACUCCAAAAAAUAAAUUUAUUGUUAGUCUAGCAUAUGCUCAUUGAAAUUGACUUAUGUUUUAUUUUAAAAAAUCAUGUAGGAUCUGGUACAUGGGGCGGGCAAAAGGGUAUCAUCAGCUUAAGAAGUAAAGAAGUGAGCCUUCCAUUUGUGUGGGUGAUAACAUCUUUUUCCUAGAUCGUACCUCAAAAUUCAGGCUCUCCAUGAAAACAAAGAUAAUCUGAAUAAAAAUUGUGUGUUGGGAAAUGUAUCAAGUGACCUUCAGUUAAGAAAAGCACAGGCUGUUUAUUAGCACAACUUGCUUCAUUAAAUAAUUCGUGGCUUUUUCUGCCACUGGGGUUCUUUUCGUUUUGAAUUCAGCUUGUGUUUGGUUCCUCGGUCUUGUACCCCUUCAGUUCGCCGGCGACGUAAUGGUGAUACCCUUUGUUUUUUGUAUCAUACCUUUUGUGAAUUGUGACAACCAUCCCGUAAUCAUUGUGGCCUCAGCAGAAGUUUUGAACAAUCUUUGCAGCCACUGUUGGGGUGUGUACCAGCAGCCUGGAAGUGACCAGCAGAGCUGACAAAAGCACCCCCUGCUCUGCCCACCUCCGCAGAGUCCUGUCCUCAUCAGAAACGGUAUCGCGGAUGCUCCUCAGGUAGGCGUAGGCAGACUUCAUUGUGUGUUAGCAGUGACAGUGAUGUCUGUACCUAUCUGUGAGUGAGACCCAUUCAUGACACACUAGAAAUGUGUACAUUCUUUUGUUUUCCAUCACGGGUAUAGGUCUUCUGCCAUGAAAGAGAACUAUCAAGGAAAUUCCUGAAAACAAGAUUUGUAAAUUCGAUUUGACCCUCCCAAAUUCAGGGCUGCUCUUUGCAGUGGUCCCUGGCCCAGCAGGUGGCCGGCGUGGCUCCUGUUGGCUCAUGCCAGUGUUGUGCUGGACCCUCGAGUAUGUGACUGUCACCCUUGUCCAAGACUGGUUUUUAACAGUCUUGAUUUGUCAUUUUGAUGCUUUGAAUACUAUAAGGAAAAUGCCACGAAUACCAUAUAAAUACCACACCAAUCUGUUGAACAUAUCUGUGUUUUCUGACAUGGGACCUGCAGAAUAGUAUUUCUUUUAAAUCCUGCAACUUUAUUAUCUAGUAGAAUUCCAAGUAGGUCUGCUUAGACACAUAUUCAGUGAAGAUUGUAUUGUGUGUGAUAUUAUCCUAUCUUUAAUAAAGUCCUACUACUGAAAAACAGGGAUUUGCAAUGAAAAUCAUAGCUAAAUAGGCAGGUUUAGAAAGUUCAAAAUAUUGGAAGUGCUAGAAGGCUGCAACUUGUAAAAUUGUACUCCCCAAGUUCAGUAGGAUAGUAGAGAAGUCGUGCUAAGUUGAUUUCAUUGAAAUGUCACGUCUCACAUCCUGUGGUCCAAAGGUACUAGUUUGUUUUGUGGAAUAAUUUUCUGUUCACUUGCUGAUAAGAAAUUUAGCAGUCAGAAGUAAUUUUUAAUUAAUAACCUUUCUUUUUAAAAGUUGCUUUAUGGUUUACAAGUAAUACUGAUGCAAAAAGGAUUUGUUAACCUAAAUUAAGUAGCACGCACUUUGUUUACAUGCUUCAGUAUAUUGUGGGGUUGGUCCCUUCUCACGAACCCAGGACCUGUGCUUGGGGAACAUUUUGCCAUCAUGCUGUUCUCUUGUACCAAGGAUCAGUGAAAGUGUUUUAUCUUUUUUAUGUAGUUUGUAUUGACUGGAUUUUAUAACUGUAAGAAAACAGAAACAGAGUGUUGUAUUUUGAUCUGAAAUUUGUGUAUGCUAAAGUAAUUUUGUUUUAUGUAUUGGAAGUUCACUUAAAAACUUGAAAUAUUUUCUAGAAGGGUACCACACAAAAGGAAUCAUCUUUAAGCUGUUUAAUUAACCUAAUAAAAUAAUUUGAUGGGGAAGGCA